GCUCUGGGAGUACGACAUGGCGCGCGAGCUGCGGGCGCUGCUGCUGUGGGGCCGCCGCCUGCGGCCUUUGCUGCGGGCGCCGGCGCUGGCGGCCGUGCCGGGAGGAAAACCAAUUCUGUGUCCUCGGAGGACCACAGCCCAGUUGGGCCCCAGGCGAAACCCAGCCUGGAGCUUGCAGGCAGGACGACUGUUCAGCACGCAGACCGCCGAGGACAAGGAGGAACCCCUGCACUCGAUUAUCAGCAGCACAGAGAGCGUGCAGGGUUCCACUUCCAAACAUGAGUUCCAGGCCGAGACAAAGAAGCUUUUGGACAUUGUUGCCCGGUCCCUGUACUCAGAAAAAGAGGUGUUUAUACGGGAGCUGAUCUCCAAUGCCAGCGAUGCCUUGGAAAAACUGCGUCACAAACUGGUGUCUGACGGCCAAGCACUGCCAGAAAUGGAGAUUCACUUGCAGACCAAUGCCGAGAAAGGCACCAUCACCAUCCAGGAUACUGGUAUCGGGAUGACACAGGAAGAGCUGGUGUCCAACCUGGGGACGAUUGCCAGAUCGGGGUCAAAGGCCUUCCUGGAUGCUCUGCAGAACCAGGCUGAGGCCAGCAGCAAGAUCAUCGGCCAGUUUGGAGUGGGUUUCUACUCAGCUUUCAUGGUGGCUGACAGAGUGGAGGUCUAUUCCCGCUCGGCAGCCCCGGGGAGCCUGGGUUACCAGUGGCUUUCAGAUGGUUCUGGAGUGUUUGAAAUCGCCGAAGCUUCGGGAGUUAGAACCGGGACAAAAAUCAUCAUCCACCUGAAAUCCGACUGCAAGGAGUUUUCCAGCGAGGCCCGGGUGCGAGAUGUGGUAACGAAGUACAGCAACUUCGUCAGCUUCCCCUUGUACUUGAAUGGAAGGCGGAUGAACACCUUGCAGGCCAUCUGGAUGAUGGACCCCAAGGAUGUCCGUGAGUGGCAACAUGAGGAGUUCUACCGCUACGUCGCGCAGGCUCACGACAAGCCCCGCUACACCCUGCACUAUAAGACGGACGCACCGCUCAACAUCCGCAGCAUCUUCUACGUGCCCGACAUGAAACCGUCCAUGUUUGAUGUGAGCCGGGAGCUGGGCUCCAGCGUUGCACUGUACAGCCGCAAAGUCCUCAUCCAGACCAAGGCCACGGACAUCCUGCCCAAGUGGCUGCGCUUCAUCCGAGGUGUGGUGGACAGUGAGGACAUUCCCCUGAACCUCAGCCGGGAGCUGCUGCAGGAGAGCGCACUCAUCAGGAAACUCCGGGACGUUUUACAGCAGAGGCUGAUCAAAUUCUUCAUUGACCAGAGUAAAAAAGAUGCUGAGAAGUAUGCAAAGUUUUUUGAAGAUUACGGCCUGUUCAUGCGGGAGGGCAUUGUGACCGCCACCGAGCAGGAGGUCAAGGAGGACAUAGCAAAGCUGCUGCGCUACGAGUCCUCGGCGCUGCCCUCCGGGCAGCUAACCAGCCUCUCAGAAUACGCCAGCCGCAUGCGGGCCGGCACCCGCAACAUCUACUACCUGUGCGCCCCCAACCGUCACCUGGCAGAGCACUCACCCUACUAUGAGGCCAUGAAGAAGAAAGACACAGAGGUUCUCUUCUGCUUUGAGCAGUUUGAUGAGCUCACCCUGCUGCACCUUCGUGAGUUUGACAAGAAGAAGCUGAUCUCUGUGGAGACGGACAUAGUCGUGGAUCACUACAAGGAGGAGAAGUUUGAGGACAGGUCCCCAGCCGCCGAGUGCCUAUCAGAGAAGGAGACGGAGGAGCUCAUGGCCUGGAUGAGAAAUGUGCUGGGGUCGCGUGUCACCAACGUGAAGGUGACCCUCCGACUGGACACCCACCCUGCCAUGGUCACCGUGCUGGAGAUGGGGGCUGCCCGCCACUUCCUGCGCAUGCAGCAGCUGGCCAAGACCCAGGAGGAGCGCGCACAGCUCCUGCAGCCCACGCUGGAGAUCAACCCCAGGCACGCGCUCAUCAAGAAGCUGAAUCAGCUGCGCGCAAGCGAGCCUGGCCUGGCUCAGCUGCUGGUGGAUCAGAUAUACGAGAACGCCAUGAUUGCUGCUGGACUUGUUGACGACCCUAGGGCCAUGGUGGGCCGCUUGAAUGAGCUGCUUGUCAAGGCCCUGGAGCGACACUGACAGCCAGGGGGCCAGAAGGACUGACACCACAGAUGACAGCCCCACCUCCUUGAGCUUUAUUUACCUAAAUUUAAAGGUAUUUCUUAACCCGA